GACGGAGAGGGCCACCGCCCAGCAAUAGACGGUGCCUCAGCCUGCCGAGCCGCAGUUUCCGUGGUGUGAGUGAGUCCGGGCCCGUGUCCCCUCUCCCGCCGCCGCCAUGGGCUGCACGUUGAGCGCCGAAGACAAGGCGGCAGUGGAGCGAAGCAAGAUGAUCGACCGCAACUUACGGGAGGACGGGGAAAAAGCGGCCAAAGAAGUGAAGCUGCUGCUACUCGGUGCUGGAGAAUCUGGUAAAAGCACCAUUGUGAAACAGAUGAAAAUCAUUCAUGAGGAUGGCUAUUCAGAGGAUGAAUGUAAACAAUAUAAAGUAGUUGUCUACAGCAAUACUAUACAGUCCAUCAUUGCAAUCAUAAGAGCCAUGGGACGGCUAAAGAUUGACUUUGGGGAAGCUGCCAGGGCAGAUGAUGCCCGGCAAUUAUUUGUUUUAGCUGGCAGUGCUGAAGAAGGAGUCAUGACUCCAGAACUAGCAGGAGUGAUUAAACGGUUAUGGCGAGAUGGUGGGGUACAAGCUUGCUUCAGCAGAUCCAGGGAAUAUCAGCUCAAUGAUUCUGCUUCAUAUUAUCUAAAUGAUCUGGAUAGAAUAUCCCAGUCUAACUACAUUCCAACUCAGCAAGAUGUUCUUCGGACGAGAGUGAAGACCACAGGCAUUGUAGAAACACAUUUCACCUUCAAAGACCUAUACUUCAAGAUGUUUGAUGUAGGUGGCCAAAGAUCAGAACGAAAAAAGUGGAUUCACUGUUUUGAGGGAGUGACAGCAAUUAUCUUCUGUGUGGCCCUCAGUGAUUAUGACCUUGUUCUGGCUGAGGACGAGGAGAUGAACCGAAUGCAUGAAAGCAUGAAACUGUUUGACAGCAUUUGUAAUAACAAAUGGUUUACAGAAACUUCAAUCAUUCUCUUCCUUAACAAGAAAGACCUUUUUGAGGAAAAAAUAAAGAGGAGUCCGUUAACUAUCUGUUAUCCAGAAUACACAGGUUCCAAUACAUAUGAAGAGGCAGCUGCCUAUAUUCAAUGCCAGUUUGAAGAUCUGAACAGAAGAAAAGAUACCAAGGAGAUCUAUACUCACUUCACCUGUGCCACAGACACGAAGAAUGUGCAGUUUGUUUUUGAUGCUGUUACAGAUGUCAUCAUUAAAAACAACUUAAAGGAAUGUGGACUUUAUUGAGAAGCAUGGAUGUUAGUGAAAGUUACUACAGUGUGGAGUGUUGAGACCAGACACCUUUUGCUGUCUCAUGGGGCAGCUACAAGCAUGAACGGGACCAGGGAAUGGCAGCAGCAUGCAGAAUCUUAGCACUCUUUAGCACAAUAUUUUGUAUUAGGGAACUUUUAAUUGACAUGAGAUGCUAAAGUCAGACAUUGGAAUUGGAAGAACUAUAAAGUGUGAUUCGAUCGUCAAGACAUCACUUGGAUUUCUUAAUCUUAAAUGCUUAUGGAAGAUGUGAAGUUGAGGUGCUGCAUUCUAGAACUUCAAUAUGUAGCUUACUCUUUUUUUCCCCCCUUCUUAAACCACCAGUGGUUCAUUUUUAAGGUUUUUUCAUCAAGAGAAGAAUAACUUUACUAAAUUUUAUUUCUUUAUUUGCAAAAGAAUCUUUAUUAAAACAAACAAUCUUAACUAUGCACAUGAUGUGACCAGAUCAUCUUGAAAAUAUUCCUCUUUAGUAGGAACUCUUUGUUUUUAACUCUUGGUAUGGUCAGAAUAUAAUACUUCCAUAAUUACUUAUAAUUCUUUCCGGUUACUGGGGCUAUAAAUACAACUUUUUAAAUGAAAUUUAUGUUAUUAUCCUGCUCAAAGUACCAUUAUGGUUUCCAUAUGGUAAUUACAUUGGAAAGUUCUGCAAUAAGAUUCUAGUUCUCUCUUUUCUUUAAGCUUAUGGUUGAAGGUUAACCUUGUUUGUGCAGAUUACCAAAUUACUGCUGAUGUAGUAUGAUAAAGUCAGCUUCUUGGAUACAGACACACCCAGGGCAGCUGCCAAUCAGAAAUGCAAAUUGCUAAAUUCCAAACAGAACCAGUGACUUUGCUGCUACAUAUUUACUAAAUUGACCACUUUGAUUCUUGCUUGUUUGUCUCAGUUAUAGGGAGUUUUGUACAUGGUGCCUCUUGUUUUCCAUCUUCAUGGCCUUUUCUGUUGAGAAACAUCUAAAGUGUAUUAACAGUGCAUGCUUUUACUUUGUAAAUGUGGUGCCAAAUCCCUGUUUGCCAUCGUUUUUACUGUACCGAUGUUAACUGUAGUAAUCCUUAGCCAGUAUGUUCUUUUGCUGAAACUGUUGCAUUUUGGGACUUUUUUCCACUUUGUCAUGUGUACAUUUUUAAUCUGUUAUAGUUGGCGGCAGUAUUAAAAUGGUGAGUAAAGAGCCCAGGUUUGCUCCUGUUUGUAACUAGUCUUUUCUGGAAAUACUGUCUUCUGUUUCCUUUUGCCUUUGCAGAAUGUGCUUUAGCCUUUGUCUGAGAAUGGGUUUAGGUAGAAGGGUUUCCUGAAAGUCUAGUCUUUUGGUGUAAUAGUAUUGUUGAACCUUAGGUUUUAUGUUAUAUCUGCAUAUGAGUGAUAUGUGAUCAUGAUUCAUUUUGCAGAUUUACAUUUUGCUUGUGUGGAAAGUUACGUUCACUUCAACCUACAGACCCUUUUGUAUAAUGUACAGCAAAUGUCAUUAAAUAUUGAAUGCUCUAUUGGGGGAAGACAAAUGAAGAGAAUGCAUUUUGAGCAUUUCAAAUCAGUAGUUUGGGCAGUGCCUUUUGGGGUCCAAUCUUUUUGGAUUGGAUUCUAUUUCAUCUUUUGAUGUGACUUUUCACUAGUUUACAAAAAAAAGGUUGGUGGUCAACAAAAAAAGCAAGUCAUAGCAGUUCAGUGCCUUUGUUGGUAGUUUUUAACUUUUUUUGUGAUUCUUUUUGGAAAAUCAUAGCUUACAGAUGGUAUAACUGUAUUAUAUAAUGGAAUUUUCUUUAGGUGUGGGAAAACUUGAUCUGAAAGAAAAUUAUCAGCUUCAAUUGGCGAUUGAUUCAGUGCCCACAAUGUAAACAGGGUUGGUAGUUGUUACUCAUUUUGAAUAUACCUUUUCCUUAUUGUAUUCUGUAAUAUAGGAUCCUGGAAAUGAGACCUGGUGGAAUAUUAUUUUCAACUGUAGUCUUUCUAUACUGUGGACUAAUGAAAUGGUGUUGUUGAUAAUCUAAAAUAACCAAUAAUCCAAAAAAGUUCAUUUUACUUUGAAUUUGUAUUUUCAUUUGAAUAUCUAUCUGAUAUGUUAAAUUUUUAGCCCUUCUGUUAAAGAAAAAUAGCAGGUCCCCAUUUUUCUGCCUCUGUACCAUUUACAUUUGCUCUCUGUUUGUUAACAUGAAGAUCACUCUUAUUUCACCAUCCCAAAUAACUUAUCUAAAUGCACAUUCCUUGAGGACACAGGGAGACAAUUUAAGUCAGUAGUUUUUAAUAUGACUUAAGUAAAAAUCACUUGGACCCAUCUAAGGGAUUGACUUUUGGCUGGUGGGCUGGCAAUCGAUUUUUUUUUUUUUUUUUUUUUUUUGAGACGGAGUCUCGCUCUGUCGCCCAGGCUGGAGUGCAGUGGCGCGAUCUCGGCUUAUUGCAAGCUCUGCCUCCCGGGUUCAUGCUAUUCUCCUGCUGGGACUACCAGGUUCCUGCCACCACGCCCAGCUAAUUUUUUUGUAUGUCUUAGUAGAGACGGGGUUUAACCGUGUUAGCCAGGAUGGUCUUGAUCCCCUGACCUCGUGAUCUGCCUGCCUCAGCCUCCCAAAGUGCUGGGAUUACAGGCGUGAGCCACCGCACCUGGCUGGCAAUUUAUAAUUUUUAAAAGGUGAUUCUGAUUACCAGCCAGGCUUGCAAAUCACUGGUUUGUAUUGAAAUAAAAGAUAUUUUCUUGUAGCAGGGCUAAAAUGUGGGAUGAAACAUUAAAUCUACUAGCCUGAAAAAAAACUUUGGCAUUUGUAAUCAAAGAAGCUGAAAGUUGCCUUGUGUGUUUCCUCUGAAGAAUGCUGGAGAUUUGUGAUGGAUAAUGUUUCAGAAUUCAGGUGCCUAUGCUUUGGACCAUCAAAGAAGCCAUUAGUCUCUGUGUAAAGAAGAAGUAUUCUUAAUGGACAGUCCCCCCUAACCUUAUAAAUUCAGCUUUGCAACAGAUUUCACCUCCUAGCAUGAAAAUUCCAAAAACUUUAACAAUUACUCAUAAGUGGAUCUUGAGAUGACAUUUUCAUCUUGGACAGUUUGAAUUCUAAAUCUCUAGUUCACAGUGAAUCGUUUUUUAAAUUUUUACUGAUGGAUCGUUAUUUUUCACAAGGUACUACAUUCUUACAAUGUAAGACUAGAUGGACCAAAAUUUUAAAAAAAACUUCUUGCCUUGUUUUUUUAAUUUUCAUAUAUAUUCUAUUUGUUGUAUAUACACAUUAGACUAUUUUAAAAUAACAGCUGGUUUUUGUAAUUCAUUCAUUCACCCUAUAUUCUUAUAUUCUGCUCAUUAUUCUCUCAUUUAUAGCUGUGACAUUCUUUGGACAUUACUUGCCUGGCCUGAUUAGUUACUUAAUAUAAUUUAUUCAUUUGCUUAGCAUGUGUGACAUAGUUCUGGAAUUUCCUGUUGCAGAACUCCUUGCUGUAUUGCAGUCAUAUAUAAGGUAAAGUCAGUCUCUUGUUCCUAUUAAAAAGCUACCAUUGAUUAUUUUCCCUUUUUACAUGUUCAAAAAAAAAAAAAUAAGCAACCCUCUACUCAUUUGUAUAAACCUAAAACGUCACUGUUUUCCUUGAGCGUUAGUACUUGUGGGUUCUUUCCUUUUCAUGUGUAAUACUGAUUUUAAGAGCAAUGAUCUUAGUUUGCCAGUGCCAGGUAAUUAUUGUGUUCUACUUUAGGCUUCGUAGUGCAAAUCAGGGAUCUGACCUGGAUCAGCCUCAGCUCUUUACAUAGCUUUAUGAUCAUCAUAUUUUGUUGUAUUGCUCCCAACAAGCACAAGAGAAAAAGGCAGGCUUCCUAGAGACCUCAAGUUGAAAGUUGAUUUUGCUGACAACUAUCAGGGAGUAAAAGAAAGCCUUUUUCAGGCACUGGAGAACUAACUUUAAUGAUGAUCAAGGUCUUUAUGCCUUUAUCUUUUAGUUUUUAAGAUCAUUUCUCUCCCUCCUUUCCCCCCAGUUUUCUCAACAUUUAUGAGUUAGUUCUGCUGAGAACAACAUACUUCAGAACAUGUCAGGAUAGGGCAGUUUUUUCUUGUUUUUCUUUUUUCUUUUUUUGAGACAGUCUUGCUCUGUUGCCCAGGCUGGAGUACAGUGGCACGAUCUCUGCUCACUGCAACCUUUGCCUCUUAGGUUCAAGCGAUUCUUGUGCCUCAGCCUCCCAAGUAGCUGUGAUUACAGGCAUGUGCCACCACAUCUGGCUAACUUUUGUAUUUCUAGUAGAGACAGGGUUUCACCAUGUUAGCCAGGCUGGUCUCAAACUCCUGACCUCAAGUGAUUUGCCUGCCUUGGCCUCCCAAAGUGCUGAGAUUACAGAUGUGAACCACUCCACCCACUCAGGGCAGUUUUUUUUCUGAUACCAUAUCAGGCCUAGGCCUGGGCUGACUCAAAUCUUCUCAGGAAUAAGAGGUAAGAAGGAAUGUUAAACAGCAGUAGUUACCUGGGGUACAUGGUUAAUUUGAUUUAGCAGAUUCUUUGGCUAAACCCUAGUAAAUUAAAAUGUCUGAGCCAGGUCAUGGGAAUAUACAUGUUUUUAAUACAUUCCUUAGGUGAUUUUGAUGUAGCCAAUCUGGGCCAACAUUUGGGGACAACUGAGUAGGACCUAAUACAGGUUGAAUAGCCCUUAUCCAAAUCUCUUGGGACCAGAAGUGUUUGAGAGUUCAGAUUUUUGUGAGGUUUUGAAAUAUUUGCAUUAUAUACUUAUUGGUUCGGGAUUCCAAAUCCAAAAAUCUGAAAUCCAAAAUGCCCCAGUGUGUGCUUCCUUUGAGUGUUAUGUUGUUACCCAAAAAGCUUUUGAUUUUGGAGCAUUUUAGAUUUUGGAUUUUCAGAUUUGAAAUGCUCAAUCUAUAUUAAAGAUCAACACAGGCUGAGCACAGUGGCUCAUGUCUGUAAUCCCAGCACUUUGGGAGGCCGAGGUAAGCAGAUCACUUGAGGUCAGGAGUUUGAGACCAGCUUGGCCAACAUGGUGAAACCCCGUCUUUACUAAAAAUACAAAAAUUAGCCAGGCAUGGUGGUGGAUGCCUGUAAUCCUAGCUACUCGGGAGGCUGAGGCAGGAGAAUCGCUUGAACCUGGGAGGCAGAGGUUGCAGUGAGCCGAGAUCGCACCACUGAAUUCCAGCCUGGGCGACAGAGUGAGUCUGUUUUUUUUUUGUUUUUUUUUAAAGUCAACACAAAUAUUGAAAAUAAGCAACUUCAGUGCACAAAUAAGCUCAAAAUCACUAGUGAGUGAUCUAUUUUUUGCCAAUAAGAAGUACCAUUUGUACAUGACUUAAAGUGCCUUCCACCAAGAAAAUUAUUGAAAACUGUUGGGUCACAUAACAUUCCUACACUUUGGAUACAGAGUAUUUAGUUUUAUACAAAAUUAAGACAACAAGAAACCUAGGAUGUCCAAACAUUCAUUUCAUUUAUUUUACUGCAUUUAUUUAUGCAGUGAAAAUUGAAAGAUACACCAAAUUAAAGAUAAAACCCUGUGACAGAUAACAGUAUAUGUAAUAACAUGAAUAUUUAUUUACACUUGGUAGAGAAAGCAAAGCUAGCUAGCUCUAAACUAGAAUGAAAGUCGUUUUGAAAUGGGUACGGGGGUAUAUAAGGGGAAUGAUUGAGUCACAUGUAAAAGCCUUUGUAUGCCCAGUGCUAGUGUUUUCCUGAAAUCUAGUGAGAAUCACAAGGUACCAGAAAUAAUCAAAUAAUAAAUAUUAAUACACUGCUGGGAUAGAAGUAUCUCAGUGUACCAGCAUUCACUAAGCUAUAAAAUCUGUGACAGCAGGAAUAUUAAAUUAUGAACAACCUGGUUUAUCUGUCUCCUCUUAUCUUUUACCUCUCCCUACGCCCAAAAUUCUCCUUAGGUUAUCCAGACAUUUUUACUAAGAUGCUUAUUUAUAUGUAAGAGAGAUUUCCAGUAGAUACAACAAAACACAAGAAAUCACCUGUUCUGUUUAUUCUUGCUCAUGUAGGAUAAAGGUCCUGAGACCUCUCAGAAUCUUACGAGGUUGGAGAGUUGUUUGGAAUGCUGGGUUCUGGUCUUGUCUCUGCUUCCAACCAGCUAUGGAAUCUUGUGUAUUCUUUCAGUCUUAAAUCACUCAUCUGUUAUCUAAAGAUGGACUAAAUUAUUCCUUCCUGCUGUGAUAUUCUGUGGUUCUCAUCAGAUAGAAAUAACAUAUUUGAAAAUGCUUUGUAAAUGUUAUGAUACUCAGGAUUAUACUGCACAGAAAAAAAAAAAUCCUAAGGCAGCACCAACAAAGGUAUUCAACGUAGUGGGUGGUCUUUUACAGCAUUACUUUGCCCAUAUUCAUUUUGAAGACCUGAAAUGAAGUUGAACUAUAAAUUGCUCUAAAAUUCGUGAAGCAGGGUGAAAAGGUCUUUGCUUUGUUUUACAUUUAAAUCCAGCUGUCUAUUUUCUGCUUAUACUAGUGCUUUUUCAUGGCAAAAAGACAGAAAAGUUCCCUUCUGCAGUCUCCAGUGUCUUCUGACCUCACAGAAAUGUUUUCAUGCUUUUACCUAGCAGGACCACCAGAGGCUCUGUCACACUUGCAGUCCCUGGCCCAACACCGAAAUCCUUCUGGAAUCUGUGCUCUGGGGGCUGUGCCGGGUAGAGAGGGCAGUGGGAGGUAAGAGCUCUUCACCCUUCACCACCUUCUCCACCCAGCAUGGCCGGCACACUUUGGUCUACGGCACAUCUCCAAGUAUAGAGUGGGUUUUGAAUGCUGUUAUGUCUCACCGUGGGGAUGGGAAGGAAUACUCUGUUUUGGACUAUUUGGAGGUACAUGUGAGUGGAUUUUAUUACCAGAGUAGGAACUGUUUCAAGUUAAUGUGUCUUUUAUGUUGCUUUUAAGACAACUUUUGUGCCGCUUUUAUCCAUUCUUCCUUUUAUCCACAGAAAUACAAAUUUCUAAUUAUAGUAUAUUUUUUCUAUUUUUAAAAUUGUGAUAAAGCAUAUAUAACAAAAUUUGCCAUCUUAAGUGUACAGUUCAGUGGCAUUAAGUACAUUCACACUGUUGCACAGCCAUCACCACCAUCCAUUUCCAGAACUUGUUUUCAUCUUCCUGAACUGAAACUCUGUACCUGUUAAACAGUAACUCCCCAUGCCCCACCUUCUUUCAGCCCCUGGUAACCAGCAUUUUCCUUUGUCUCUAUGAAUUUGACUAUUUUAGAUACCUCAUAUAAGUGGAAUCAUAGUAUUUGUCCUUUUGUGUCAAUCAUAUUGUAUUUUUGUCUAAAAAAGGAAAACUAUCAGAUUUAUGUGAAAUGUAACGUAAUUUACAUUUGAUUUACUGUUAGUAAUGUCUCUUUAAUCAUGCUAUGCUAGGGAAGUACAUUAUGGUCUCUCCCUCUAAGAAUAUGAAGAGGAAAUUUUACCUUCAACAAACAAGCAAACUUAGUUAUAUUUUUGUGAUUUUAUGCUGUUUUCAUAUUCUAUUUUGAGAUCUAUUUGUCUUAGCUUGGAGGUGGUUUUGUUAAAUGUCCACGAUUUAGAGACGGCAUAAUGAAAAAAUGACCAAGAAUUUGGUUGGGAAUGGGAGGAGCUUAGAAGAACAAGAAAUUGGCUUUGAUUUUAUAGUGUAUGGUGCUCUGUUGGUAGCUGGACAUCAUCACAGGCUUUGGAUUGAGAAGACCUGUUCUGGAGUUCUAGUUCUGCUACUGCCUAGCGUUGUGAUCUUGAUGAAGAUACUCUUCCUUCCUGGGCUUCAGUUUUUGAUCUAUAAAUUGCUAGUGAUGGGGCUGGACUAUUUUUAAGUUUGUUCUAACUUUAGCAGUCUUAAGAAUUAAGGUUGCAUGCCAGAAAAUAGGGUUAAAUAUUUGUUUCUGAUCUGGUUACAAAAAAAAAAAAAACUUGAUGGCUUAAAGUAAAUAAAAAUUCAACAGUACGGUGUAAAUUUAAAA